ACACUGGGGAGAAACCUUUCGAGUGUCCGGAAUGUGGAAAAGCUUUCACCCACCAGUCAAACCUCAUUGUACACCAGAGAGCACAUAUGGAGAAGAAGCCCUAUGAGUGCAGUGAAUGUGGAAAGACAUUUGCCCAAAAGUUUGAACUCACCACACACCAGAGAAUUCAUACAGGAGAGCGACCCUAUGAGUGUAACGAAUGUGCAAAAACCUUCUUUAAGAAGUCAAACCUUAUCAUACAUCAGAAGAUUCACACGGGGGAGAAACGCUAUGAGUGCAGUGAAUGUGGAAAAUCCUUUAUCCAGAACUCACAGCUCAUCAUACACAUGAGAACUCAUACAGGAGAGAAACCCUAUGAAUGUACUGAGUGCGGCAAAACUUUCAGCCAGAGGUCAACUCUUAGAUUACACUUGCGAAUCCACACAGGAGAGAAACCAUAUGAGUGUUCCGAAUGUGGGAAGGCCUUUAGCAGGAAGUCCCGACUCAGUGUCCAUCAGAGAGUUCACAUCGGGGAGAAACCCUGAAACUCCAGCCAGGUCUUACUGUGGAAAACUCCUGCCAGAACUCUUCAAGCGGGUGAAAAACCUCAUGACAGUAUUGAGGGAACAUGGGAAUUCAUACUGAGAUGCAAUCUCUCAACUCAAAAAUGUAUUAAAAAUAGGAUCCCAUGAGAACAUUAUACUGGAAGUUACAUGUGAUACCCAGCUAAAGAAUACAUAUCAGAAUAUAUCCAGUUGUAAAUAGCCAUACCCAGUUGUACUACAAUGAGCUUUUUAAAAUCUUGAAUGAAUUGAGUAUUCUAGACAGCAGCAUAAGAAAUAUACAAACAGUAUCCUAUGAAUUUAGUGGUUUUAUGUGGAUAUGCCACAAAACACAAGUGGUAUGCUUUAGAUCUGCACAUGUGAAUUUAGCAUAAUCACUGGGAAUUUGAAAUUCUUGUCCUCUGUGAUAAUUAGGACAUAACAAGAUUUUCCAUACUAAACAUCACAUGUGUUUUUCAGUAUCUCUGCAAUCCAGUAUGCAUUCCAAAUGAAAUGUGUAACAUUUAAAGUAGCAUGGAACCUACGUCUUUCCCUACUGCUUGCUGGCAUAUAUCAGUUGGUAUGAACAUUGUUCUUGAGCUGCCUCUUAGGAAACAGAAGACAGUGUUGAAGUUUUCCCUGCUUCUGGUUUGCUGAAGAUUUUCUAGAAGCACUAUUUACACAAAUAUGCAAAUGUGAAAUAACCGAUCUAUAACGUGAAGGAGGCAGACAUGAGCUGUACUACUCAGUAUGCACCACAGAAUAAGAGUUUGCCGUGUAAAGACAAUAUCCCCAUUCGUCAUGCUCUUAUUUUCCCGUGGGAUAUUUGCAUACAAAUGCAUGUCUGUUACCAAAAUAUUGUGUAACACAGACAGAAACCACCUGUUUUUGUCUUUCCUUGUUUCCCUUAAUAUUUCAUGAAUUGUCUAGCAAAAAUGGUAGGAUGCUUCUGUAGUUCACAAAUGUUACAUUUCAGAGACUUUAGAGGAAAAAUUAUUUUAAAUAACUGUCAACUGUUUCAUUGCUUUUUAAAUUUUUCACGUGCAUAACCCCCUUUAGAAGUAAAUUUUUACACUAUUUUGUUGUUUAAAGGAGGCAUUUCUACUUCCUUGAGUUUUGCUGUUGCCAACCUAAAACAUUUCCCUUUGGAACAUGAGUUAUAAGUUAUUACUUUUCCUUUACAUGUUUACACUUUUAUAAAAAUCAGAUUUUUCAGUGGUCUCUCCAGAUAUUAACAAGAAUUGUUGUGUAACUCAAAGAUUUGCUUUUAUAGACUUGAUUUCAAAUUCUUAAGUUCAGCCUUUCCCUAUCAAUCACAAAUCAUGUAUUGGAAAUUAUAAAUGGCAACCAAAAACUGGCUUUUAAAAAAUAUUUUUGGAUAUCAUUGAUGUGCUGUCACACUAUAUAUUGAGUGACUUUCUGAACAAAUUUAUCCAGAACAUCCAUAGCCCAAUAAGCUUUUGUCUAAGUUGUCAUCUUACUUACUCACAAAGGAGGGGAAAACGUUAUUUUCAUAGCUGCUUUUAGAAAUGUAAAUUGUAACAGCCUCCUUGGACAACAUUGUGAGUCUGUUUUAACAUUAAUAUACUCUUACAACCUAGGAAUCUCCUGGGAAUCUAUCCCUAAGGAAUAAAAAGCGCCAGCACUUAAGAUUAUAUGUUUACUAAUGUAUAUUGUAUUUUUUGGUAAGGACCAAAAAAACAAACAAAAAAAAGACCAUCAGUAAGGGAAUGGAUGAAUAAAUUGUGGUAAAAACAUACCAUGGCUGAAUGGUAUUUCCUUGAAAAGAAUGUGUGGGAACAAACUCCAAACUUCUCUAGGUCAAAUGAGGAAAGCAAGAGGGGAGAGAGAGAGUGUAUGUGUGUGUGUAGCAGUUUUUAUAAAAUAAAGAUAAACCCUUAUA